CCGCCCUCCAGCGCGCGGACGUGGUAGGCGGCCAAGCGUUUUUGGCUGCUUCCCGGGAAGCCGUUGGUCGCGCUUGCGUAGUGAACCGCUGAGGCUGUGUUGAGCGCUCCUUCUCCGCGCAACUCCCGGCUUCGACACCGCCUUCCUUCCUAUGAAUCCUUAAUUUAACGUGGUCACAGUCAGCUUAAGACCGGCACCUCUCGGGCUCCGUCUUGUAGGACCUCGGCCUGGCUUCGAGGGCUUCCAUACAGGUCACCGCAGGCUCUUUCAACUCCCGCCGCUUCCAGGCCCGCGUAACCAGACCACAACACUGAACUUGGAGCACCAAGAACAGGAGCCCCACCCUGUUUGGCCAGGAUGCCUUUGGGACGCUUGGCAGGGAGCGCCCGCUCCGAGGAGGGAAGCGAGGCAUUUCUGGAGGGAAUGGUGGAUUGGGAGCUGAGUAGGCUGCAGCGACAAUGCAAAGUGAUGGAAGGGGAGAGGCGGGCCUACAGCAAGGAAGUCCACCAGCGCAUCAACAAGCAACUUGAGGAGAUCCGGCGCUUGGAGGAGGUACGGGGCGAUCUCCAGGUGCAGAUCAGCGCAGCCCAGAACCAGGUCAAGCGGCUUCGGGACAGUCAGCGGCUGGAGAACAUGGACCGCCUGCUGAAGGGCCGGGCCCAGGUGCAGGCGGAGAUCGAGGAGCUGCAGGAGCAGACCAGGGCCCUGGACAAGCAGAUCCAGGAGUGGGAGACGCGGAUCUUUACCCACAGUAAGAAUGUCAGGUCCCCGGGAUUCAUCCUGGAUCAGAAGGUCAAGAUCAGGCGAAGGAUCAGGAUCCUAGAAAACCAGUUGGACAGGGUCACCUGUCACUUUGACAACCAGCUGGUACGGAAUGCGGCCCUGCGGGAGGAGCUGGAUCUGCUGCGGAUCGACAGGAACCGCUAUCUGAACGUGGACCGCAAGCUGAAGAAGGAGAUCCACCACCUGCAUCACCUGGUCAGCACCCUUAUCCUCUCCUCCACCUCUGCCUACGCCGUCAGGGAGGAGGCGAAGGCCAAGAUGGGCUUGCUGCGGGAGCGCGCGGAGAAAGAGGAGGCCCAGAGCGAGAUGGAGGCGCAGGUCCUGCAGCGGCAGAUCUUGCACCUGGAGCAGCUGCACCACUUCCUCAAGCUCAAGAACAACGACCGGCAGCCGGAUCCCGAUGUCCUGGAGAAGCGUGAAAAGCAGGCCGGGGAGGUGGCCGAGGGCGUCUGGAAGACCUCCCAGGAGAGGCUGGUGCUUUGCUACGAGGACGCCCUGAAUAAACUGUCCCAGCUGAUGGGGGAGAGUGACCCUGACCUGUUGGUGCAGAAGUAUCUGGAGAUCGAGGAGCGCAACUUUGCUGAGUUCAACUUCAUCAACGAGCAGAACUUGGAGCUGGAGCAUGUGCAGGAAGAGAUCAAGGAGAUGCAGGAGGCUUUGGUGAGCGCACGUGCCAGCAAGGAUGACCAGCAUUUGCUGCAGGAGCAGCAGCAGAAGGUGUUGCAGCAGCGCAUGGACAAGGUGCACUCGGAGGCUGAGCGCCUUGAGGCCCGCUUCCAGGAUGUGCGGGGACAGCUGGAGAAGCUCAAGGCUGAUAUCCAGCUCCUCUUCACCAAGGCCCAUUGCGACAGCAGCAUGAUCGAUGACCUCCUUGGGGUCAAGACCAGCAUGGGAGACCGGGACAUGGGCCUCUUCCUGAGCCUCAUUGAGAAGCGGCUGGUGGAGCUCCUGACAGUGCAGGCCUUCCUACAUGCCCAGAGCUUCACCUCCCUGGCCGACGCUGCCCUCCUAGUGCUGGGCCAGAGCCUGGAGGACCUUCCGAAGAAGAUGGCCCCACUUCAGCCCCCUGACACUCUAGAAGACCCCCCGGGUUUUGAGGCCAGCGAUGACUACCCCAUGAGCAGGGAGGAGCUGCUGAGCCAAGUGGAGAAGCUGGUGGAGCUCCAGGAGCAGGCGGAGGCGCAGCGCCAGAAGGACCUGGCCGCCGCCGCCGCGAAGCUGGACGGCACCCUGAGCGUGGACCUGGCCAGCACCCAGAGGGCCGGCUCCAGUACCGUCCUGGUGCCCACCAGGCACCCCCAUGCCAUCCCCGGGUCCAUUUUGAGCCACAAGACUAGCAGAGACCGUGGCUCUCUUGGCCACGUCACUUUUGGCGGCCUCAGCUCCAGCACUGGGCAUUUGCCCAGCCACAUCACGCACGGUGACCCCAACACUGGCCACGUGACCUUCGGCUCCACCAGUGCCUCGAGUGGGGGCCACGUGACCUUCAGACCCGUCAGCGCCAGCAGCUACCUGGGCUCCACUGGAUACGUGGGGUCCAGCAGGGGCGGAGAAAACACAGAGGGUGGUGUGGAGAGCGGAGGCACAGCGUCUGAUUCGAGCGGAGGCCUCGGGUCCAGCAGAGACCACGUCUCCAGCACCGGCCCUGCCUCCAGCACUGGCCCGGGCUCCUCCACCAGCAAAGACUCCCGGGGCUAACACGAGGGGCACGCAGCCCCCACCCUGCCCUGGCUCUCUGUGGGGUCUUUUUUUGUGUCUCUACUUCCCCUGUUUGCCUUGUGGGUCUCUGUCUUUUUCUCCCAGUGGCAGGCCUCUGUCUUUUUGCCCCUUCAACUGUUUUCAUCUGCCCUUCAUCACCGCCUCACCUGUGUCUCCCGGUUCCUUUCUCUCUGCUCCUGACACUGCUUUUCCCUCUGACUCCUGAUCUCCUGUUCUCUGGGCUUCCUGGUCAGUGUCUGUCCGUCUUGUCUCCAUAUCUGCCCCUUCCCUGUCUGCUGAGCCCUGGCCCCCUGUGGAUCCCCCACCUCCUGUUUCCGGCUCUCUCUCCUCAUCUCCAUCUCCCAGGCUCUCCACGCAUCCUGUGUCCCUGUCUCUGUAGCUCCUUACUCCCCAAGAGCCCCCCAGUGCUGACAGGUGUGGGAAAAGUCAGGGCGAAGACGCCAGGUUCAGCAUGGGAAAAUGGGACUGUGGAAAUAAAGUAUAUGUGUGGAGA